GCCUGCCAGGCCUGCCUGGAAGGCUGCAGGGAGGUUCAGGGUUUCUCUUGCUGUCCACACCUGGGCGAGAGCUGAGCGGAAGAGAAGGGGUCCUCAGAGAGACACCUUCCUGACCGGCCCCAUUCCAGCUGGAUGCCAUGUGACUCGGAGGAGCUGGUGGACACUGAACAGGAGCCGCCCAGAGGCUCUGGGGACUGGAGCCCUCGGCCGCGGCCAGGAUAGAUCCAAGGCCCAGGGUCAGAGCAGGCAGGGCUCGGCCAGUCCUCUGCCCCAAACGGGGCAUCAGGAGAGAGAGCGAGCAGAACACACUCCUGCAGCAUCCCCUGGCCCCCCGCCCCAUGAUGGAGCCCAGAGAAGCUGGACAGCACGUGGGGGCCGCCAACGGCGCCCAGGAGGAUGUGGCCUUCAACCUCAUCAUCCUGUCCCUCACCGAGGGGCUCGGCCUCGGUGGGCUGCUGGGGAAUGGGGCAGUCCUCUGGCUGCUCAGCUCCAAUGUCUACAGAAACCCCUUCGCCAUCUACCUCCUGGACGUGGCCUGCGCGGAUCUCAUCUUCCUUGGCUGCCACAUGGUGGCCAUCGUCCCCGACUUGCUGCAAGGCCGGCUGGACUUCCCGGGCUUCGUGCAGACCAGCCUGGCAACGCUGCGCUUCUUCUGCUACAUCGUGGGCCUGAGUCUCCUGGCGGCCGUCAGCGUGGAGCAGUGCCUGGCCGCCCUCUUCCCAGCCUGGUACUCGUGCCGCCGCCCACGCCACCUGACCACCUGUGUGUGCGCCCUCACCUGGGCCCUCUGCCUGCUGCUGCACCUGCUGCUCAGCGGCGCCUGCACCCAGUUCUUCGGGGAGCCCAGCCGCCACUUGUGCCGGACGCUGUGGCUGGUGGCAGCGGUGCUGCUGGCUCUGCUGUGUUGCACCAUGUGUGGGGCCAGCCUUAUGCUGCUGCUGCGGGUGGAGCGAGGCCCCCAGCGGCCCCCACCCCGGGGCUUCCCUGGGCUCAUCCUCCUCACCGUCCUCCUCUUCCUCUUCUGCGGCCUGCCCUUCGGCAUCUACUGGCUGUCCCGGAACCUGCUCUGGUACAUCCCCCACUACUUCUACCACUUCAGCUUCCUCAUGGCCGCCGUGCACUGCGCGGCCAAGCCCGUCGUCUACUUCUGCCUGGGCAGUGCCCAGGGCCGCAGGCUGCCCCUCCGGCUGGUCCUCCAGCGAGCGCUGGGAGACGAGGCUGAGCUGGGGGCCGUCAGGGAGACCUCCCGCCGGGGCCUGGUGGACAUAGCAGCCUGAGCCCUGGGGCCCCCGACCCCAGCUGCAGCCCCCGUGAGGCAAGAGGGUGACUUGGGGAAGGUGGUGGGGUCAGAGGCUGGGGCCAGCCGGACCUGGAGGAGGCCUUGGUGGGUGACCCGGUCAUGUGCUGUCAAAGUUGUGACCCUUGGUCUGGAGCAUGAGGCUCCCCUGGGAGGCAGCUGGAAAGGCAAGGUCUCUACAUGCCCAGGCAGGCGGGCCGGGUCUCUGGGGAGAAGGCCGAGGAACGUGCAUUUUUGGGAAACCUCCCCAACGGUUCACGCACUGGCACUCGAGAGCUGCUGCUGCUACCCAUUCCCUGCUCAGCUGCAGUGAGGAGACCCCGGAAAGCAAGGAAGCAAGGCCAGACGCCAGGUGAGGGGCAGGUCCAGGCCUUUCCGCAGGCCACCUCCCCUCCCACUCCAGCUUCCUCAAUGCUGCAGGUGCACCCACAGAUAACACAACCAUCCCCUCAGCUCGCCUUGUGCCCGCUGUGGAAGCUAAAUUGACCCUAAAAUGGAAGACUGCCCAAAACUUGACCCCCUCCCCGUCCUUGAUCAUCAGCCAGUUGCUCAAGGCCGUGCACCUCAGACCGGGACGAUGCAACCCUCACUCGGAGCUUCAGAAAAGCCGGCCCCAUGGGUGUCCCUGGAUAUUAGGAGGGUGCACCCUGGGUGGGUGGAGAGGCUUCUUACAGCCCCACCCAGCAGCCUGCAGCCCUGUCUCCCCACAGGACCCAGGUCUUCAGCAACCAGAAAGCUUCACACCGGCCCCAUCCAAGGCAGUUCACCCGCCUCUGUCCUGAGCAAGUCCCGCUCCAGAGGAUCCCUCUGAGGAAGGAACCCAGGCUUCACCCCUCAACAGGUUUCCGAGCUUCCGCUGAGUGCCAGGCCUGGCUGCCAUCCAGGAGCAUGUGCCAGGGGUGCUAGAGUGGGGGCUUUGGAGCCCACAGCCUGGGCUGAGCCCCGCUAGCCACCCCACUGUGCUGCCAAGGCCAUCUCUGAACAUCCCUACGCCUCUGUUUGCUGGUCUGUAAAAUAUGAGAACCCAGUGCUUUGAGGCCUGUCCAGCCUCUCGUGAGCCCAAGAGAAAUGUCUGUCGAUUCUACUGCCACCAACGCCACACAUCCAAGUCCACAGUGCAAUUCUUAGCCACAGACCAAGGCAUCUGAGAGUGUUUUCUUUGAUUUCUGACUCCGGCCUCCAUGGCUGGUGAUGGAAGGACAUUCCCUCUGGACCAUGACUGAACCAGCCCCUCUUGAGUCUGGGUGUGAGUCGCAGAUCCCUGGUCAGCACCCUGGAAUCCGGCUGCACCGGGCCCCUCCCAGCCCACACAGUGCGUUCACCUCAGGCUCCCGCACGUGCCCAGCAGGCCUGGGUCCAGGUAUCCCUUGAGACUGGGAGCCCCAGGGGCUGGACCCACCUCUCCUAGAGCACCUCCAGCCCCCACUUGGGGACUUACCUCCUCCCAAAUUAUCUCCAGCCCAGGAUCUGCACAGGGCCCUCUCUCCCCACCUCCAGGACGUGAUUAGCAACUUCAGUUCCUCAGCUGGAGAAACAAGAACAGAAAGGGAAGUGGCCUGUCCACAAAUUCCACUUUCAGCCCCAGGACAUAAACUUCCCCCAGAACAAGGAAGAACCAGGAGGAAAAGCACAGAUUCAUCUCACGGACAUGACCUCACCGUGGACGUGUUCCCGGGGAAUCCUCGUAAUAAUGUAGGAAGGUGCUCCCACUCUGCAGAUGAGCCACCAAGGCUCCGAGGGGCUAUGUGGCCGUUCAGGACCACAGGAAAGCUGCAAAGCCAGAAGGUGACUCCCAGCACCACCCUCCCACGCCACACGCUCCGCCUCACUGGACCAGGGCUGGCUCAGGUGUCCUCAGCCCCACACUGGCUCCCCCAACCCUGGCCCCAUCCCCACGCAGACCCCUUUGCUGCAUAAGGGUUCAGAGAGAUUGCGGACCCUUAGAAUGCUCACUUCUUCCCAGAGAGCCUGCUCUCAGCAUCCAGGGGAUUGGAGUGGCUCUAGAUUCCUCCUUAUUAGCCCCUUCUCGAGGAGUCCGGGAAAUGUGGCCUCAUCUGAGGUCUCCAUGGAAACUGGGCCCAGCUCGUCCCCACUCUAGUAGCUGCUGUGGCAGCAGGUAUAUGGCCUGAUGGCCCAGGAUGCUGGUGGGGUAUCCCCUUGGCCCCAGAUGUGCCAGCUUGGCCUCCAGUUCUGUGGUCCUUGAGCCCUCAGGACAUUAGGACCAUGUGGGCUGGCCUCCAAACUGGAGGCUGAGCUUCCGUCCAGGCUCCCACCUGCCCCUGCCCAGCCUGCGCCUCCUCUGACCUCCCCCGCUGCACCUCCUCUUCUGCCCCCAGAGCCACAAGGCCCCACCAGGGACCCCUGGCUGCCCUAGACCCCACCCUGCAGGACCCUGGGGCCUCACUGCUCAAAGGCCACCUCCACCUGGGUCGCAGGCAAAGCUCCUCGGUCAGUGCCCAGCCCACCCCAUCCACCCGCAACCCCGGGCCCCUGCGGGGCUGCCGCGGUCAGCACAGAAUUCCCAAGAACAGGCGGCUACUCCUGGGGGCAGCCAACAUUCCAGGGAGCCUGUGUAACCCGCUCCGUCCUCAGGGCCCAGGGAGGCUGUGGGUGAGGACUGUGUGUGUGAGGACAGGAGCGGAGACAGGCCUGCGGCCAGCUUCCCUAUCCCCUCCCCAGCGCCCGGGUACGAGUCUGUAAAUCAGCCUGCGCUGCAUGGCGUCUUCACGGGGAGAGGCAGGCUCACUCCUCAGCUAGUUCAUUAGCUCACACGCUGGAAAAAUAAAACCAAACAUCACACUUAAAACAUGA